GUUAGUUCCCGGUCACCUGAGCUCCGGGUGACGCGGCUGCGGUAGCUGCGGAUACAAGCCUUCCGCGGGUCCUGCCUGGCGACCCCGACCUCCUCCUGCUGUCUCUCCGCUCCGCCACCCCGAACCCGCCAAGGUCCUGUCCUUUUCCUCCUGUCCUUUGCCAGCGUUGGGCCGGACCGGGCCGAGCCGGGCCGCCCGGGCGCAGUCUUUAACCAUGGCGUCCCUCUUCAAGAAGAAAACCGUGGAUGAGUUUCGCUGUUGUUGCCCAGGCUGGAGUGCUGGAGUGCAAUGGCAUGAUCUCGGCUCAACGCAACCAUCACCUCCCAGAUUCAAGCGAUUCUUCUACCUCAGCCUACCGAGUAGCUCGGAUUACAGAUGUAAUAAAGGAACAGAAUCGAGAGUUACGAGGUACACAGAGGGCUAUAAUCAGAGAUCGAGCAGCUUUAGAGAAACAAGAAAAACAGCUGGAAUUAGAAAUUAAGAAAAUGGCCAAGAUUGGUAAUAAGGAAGCUUGCAAAGUUUUAGCCAAACAACUUGUGCAUCUACGGAAACAGAAGACGAGAACUUUUGCUGUAAGUUCAAAAGUUACUUCUAUGUCUACACAAACAAAAGUGAUGAAUUCCCAAAUGAAGAUGGCUGGAGCAAUGUCUACUACAGCAAAAACAAUGCAGGCAGUUAACAAGAAGAUGGAUCCACAAAAGACAUUACAAACAAUGCAGAAUUUCCAGAAGGAAAACAUGAAAAUGGAAAUGACUGAAGAAAUGAUCAAUGAUACACUUGAUGACAUCUUUGACGGUUCUGAUGACGAAGAAGAAAGCCAGGAUAUUGUGAAUCAAGUUCUUGAUGAAAUUGGAAUUGAAAUUUCUGGAAAGAUGGCCAAAGCUCCAUCAGCUGCUCGAAGCUUACCAUCUGCCUCUACUUCAAAGGCUACAAUCUCAGAUGAAGAGAUUGAACGGCAACUCAAGGCUUUAGGAGUAGAUUAGUCAAAAGAAGUCAUACUAUUUUGCUUACUUAUAAUUAUGUAGUAUAAACCAAGCACAGUGCAGAUUUCUUUUACAAAACACAUGUAUUUUGCAAAAAAAAAAAAAAUGAAGACCAUGAGUGAACAGUUGUUUCCUAACCCAUGGCUAUUUAGAAUCUUUUGCCAAAGAAUGACAAUGAUGCAAAAAUGGGAACAGUUUGGAUUUUAAUUAGAACUGUUUAGGAGUGAUGAUGUGUAAAAAGUUGACUUCUCUUUUGCAUGGCACAGAGAAAUUAUAUUCCUUACUUCAUGUCAGUUUAUGUUCUAAAUCUUUUUCACUGAAUAUAAAAAUCUUGUUAAAUGCCAUUAGGCACCAACUUAAAGAGGGUUGUAAAAAUAUUAAAAGUAUAUCGUUAAUUCUGUAUCUGUUGCUUGUCUUUUGUAAGUGAUUAUGUGUUAUGACCAUAGGUGGUUACAGCUGCCAAAUUAUUUUUAAAUGGUCAAAAAGAAGAGUGCUAUUUAAACAUCUGUCUUAAACAAAAACUGUCAUAACUUUUCUUUUUUCUUUUUCCAUUAGGAGAACAUUCUAGUUGGUAAAUUUCAAAAUGUGCUUGACACCUGCCUUAAAUAGCACAGACCUAUUGUGCACAUCUUUAAAUUAUUUCAGCUGGCAGAAAAGAAUUACAUUUAAAACUGAAAUCAAGGCCUCAAUACAAAGAUUAUCCUGGCUCUUUUCUAUCUCUGUGGGCCUAAUUGAAAUAUGUACUCUUAUUUUAGACACGCCUCUGUUAAAACAGACCAGGUUUUCCUGGUCUCAGACCUAUGAUGACUUGUCCCUUUGAUGUCACUACUGUGAAUUGAAUAUAAUUAGUAAAAAUAGACGAUGAAUAAAUAACACUUUAUAGUAAGAAAACAAUAUAUUUUGGCCAUCUAAAAAUGAGAAUUAUAAUUAUAUGAAUUAUAAUUUAAACUGUUUAAUUUUGUUUAAUGUGUAUAUUGAAUCUUCCAAAUUGAAGCCAUUAUUCUCAAUUAAGUACUACAACUAUGACAAUGCUUGACCUACAUUUCUAAAAUAAAAAUUCACAUUUUUUGAUAAAUAAACUACAGUUUUACCAGAAAUUACUAUCUAAAUGUGUAUUAGCAGUAUUUUUUAAGGUGAAAUUGCCUUGGUAUCUAAUGAAUGUGUAGACAGGGAGAUAAAAUGAAGGAUUGCCAGACUAGUUAGAAUAGAAUUUAGGAUUAGGUUAGUUUUGAAAAAUGAUGUUGUAAUAUAUGGGUUCUAACACAUCCUACCAUAAAAACUGGAGGAGAUAUGUGUAACCUGGUUAAUUUGGGAUGGUGGACAUUUUGGGCUAAUACUGACAAAAUACAUCUUAGGACUAGUAUACAUGUGACACGGAUUGCUAGGAGGAAUGAAAAACUAAACUGUAUAGUUUAUAUUCCGUAAACCAUUUUAUAAUGUUCAAAGAUUAGGUUUUGUUAUUGAUAGUAUUAAAUACACAGUUUCUCUUAACAGUGAUGGGUGAAAACAUUUUACCGGAUUAUGGAAUGUUUACCAGAACAUGUUUUGAUUCUUGAAUGUACAUAAUAAUGCCAUCUAACUUAUUUACGUUCUUGUUUACAUGUGGGAGCUUUUGUUUUCAAAAAUUAUUUUGUUAAAAAAUCUCAAUAAAGAUUUAUUAUUGUUGUUCUUUUCUUACCUUUUUUGCUCUUUUUGGUUCCUGCUAAAAUUAAAAAUUUUAUGCAUAUUUGGUAA